AGAGCGGCCGCUGCCGCCGCCAACGAACUGAGAGCCGCGUGGGGCCCAGCAGCACGCCGGCCAGGGAAGGGGGCCUAGCGAUCGGUCCGAGGGCGACGGGCCGCCAGCGGCCGCAGGGCGACGAAGACGCGGAGGAGGCGGAGCCCGGAGAGGGGUGGGGGCCGGGGAGGGUUCGGGUGGGAGGGGGUGGGGGGGGUGUCCCUGGGCUCAUGGAGCCGGCCGAGCGGGCGGGAGUCGGAGAGCCCCCGGAGCCGGGCGGGCGUCCCGAGCCGGGCCCGCGGGGCUUCGUCCCGCAGAAGGAGAUCGUCUACAACAAGCUGCUGCCCUACGCGGAGCGGCUAGACGCCGAGUCCGACUUGCAGCUGGCCCAGAUCAAAUGCAACCUGGGCCGGGCCGUGCAGCUCCAAGAGCUGUGGCCCGGGGGCCUCUUCUGGACCAGGAAACUCUCCACAUAUAUUCGACUUUAUGGGAGAAAAUUUAGCAAAGAAGAUCAUGUUCUUUUUAUUAAGUUAUUGUAUGAGCUGGUAUCAAUUCCAAAACUGGAAAUCAGCAUGAUGCAGGGAUUUGCCCGCCUUUUGAUCAACUUGUUAAAGAAAAAGGAACUUCUUUCAAGAGCUGAUUUGGAGUUACCCUGGAGACCACUUUAUGACAUGGUAGAAAGAAUAUUAUAUUCCAAGACAGAGCACCUAGGAUUAAAUUGGUUUCCUAAUUCUGUAGAAAAUAUUCUCAAAACACUCGUGAAAAGCUGCCGACCAUAUUUUCCAGCAGAUGCCACCGCUGAGAUGCUAGAAGAAUGGCGACCUUUAAUGUGCCCUUUUGAUGUAACCAUGCAAAAGGCCAUCACUUAUUUUGAAAUAUUUCUUCCUACCUCCCUUCCUCCAGAACUUCAUCAUAAAGGUUUUAAACUUUGGUUUGAUGAAUUAAUUGGCCUUUGGGUUUCAGUGCAAAAUCUCCCACAAUGGGAGGGGCAACUAGUAAAUCUCUUUGCUCGAUUGGCUACAGAUAAUAUAGGGUACAUAGAUUGGGAUCCAUAUGUACCAAAGAUAUUUACAAGAAUUCUGAGAAGCUUGAACCUCCCAGUGGGAAGCAGUCAAGUGUUAGUCCCAAGAUUUUUAACAAAUGCUUAUGAUAUAGGACAUGCUGUAAUAUGGAUCACCGCCAUGAUGGGUGGACCAAGUAAGCUAGUGCAAAAACACUUAGCUGGUUUGUUUAACAGCAUCACAUCUUUUUACCAUCCUUCAAAUAAUGGGCGCUGGCUGAACAAGUUAAUGAAACUACUUCAGCGGUUGCCAAACAGUGUUGUUAGAAGAUUGCAUCGUGAAAGAUACAAGAAGCCCUCUUGGUUAACUCCUGUGCCUGAUAGCCACAAGCUUACUGAUCAAGAUGUUACAGACUUUGUACAAUGCAUUAUUCAGCCUGUCCUCUUGGCUAUGUUUAGCAAAACCGGUAGUCUAGAAGCAGCCCAGGCUUUGCAGAAUCUUGCACUCAUGAGACCUGAAUUGGUAAUACCCCCUGUACUUGAAAGAACAUAUCCUGCAUUAGAGACAUUAACAGAACCUCACCAGCUCACAGCUACUUUAAGUUGUGUAAUUGGAGUAGCCCGCAGUUUGGUAUCAGGAGGCAGAUGGUUUCCUGAAGGUCCUACACAUAUGCUACCUCUGUUGAUGAGAGCAUUGCCUGGGGUGGAUCCAAAUGACUUUAGUAAAUGCAUGAUCACAUUCCAGUUCAUAGCAACAUUUUCUACUCUGGUGCCUUUAGUAGAUUGUUCAUCUGUACUACAAGAAAGAAAUGACCUCACAGAAGUGGAACGAGAACUUUGUUCAGCCACAGCUGAAUUUGAGGAUUUCGUCUUACAGUUUAUGGACAGAUGUUUUGGACUUAUAGAAAGUAGCACAUUGGAGCAAACAAGAGAAGAGACAGAAACUGAGAAAAUGACACACUUGGAGAGUUUGGUCGAAUUAGGUCUGUCUUCUACGUUUAGUACAAUCCUCACCCAAUGUUCCAAAGAAAUAUUUAUGGUGGCCCUUCAGAAGGUUUUUAAUUUUUCUACUUCACAUAUAUUUGAAACAAGAGUAGCAGGUCGCAUGGUGGCAGACAUGUGCCGCGCUGCUGUAAAGUGCUGCCCAGAAGAAUCUUUGAAGCUCUUUGUUCCCCACUGCUGCAGUGUUAUAACUCAGCUUACAAUGAAUGAUGAUGUAUUAAAUGAUGAAGAGCUAGACAAGGAAUUACUAUGGAAUCUUCAACUUUUGUCUGAGAUUACUCGAGUGGAUGGAAGGAAGUUGCUUCUUUAUAGGGAGCAGCUUGUAAAGAUUCUCCAAAGAACCCUACAUUUAACCUGUAAGCAGGGUUACACUCUGUCUUGUAACCUUUUGCAUCAUCUUCUCCGUUCUACCACACUUAUCUACCCUACAGAAUACUGCAGUGUGCCAGGUGGCUUUGACAAGCCUCCUUCUGAAUACUUUCCUAUCAAGGACUGGGGCAAACCCGGGGACUUGUGGAAUCUGGGAAUCCAGUGGCAUGUUCCUUCUUCAGAAGAAGUGUCUUUUGCCUUUUAUCUUUUGGACUCCUUUCUUCAGCCUGAGCUCGUCAAACUCCAGCAUUGUGGGGAUGGAAAACUUGAAAUGUCUAGAGAUGAUAUUCUACAGAGUCUGACUAUAGUGCACAACUGUUUAAUUGGCUCUGGAAACCUCCUACCUCCGUUGAAAGGAGAGCCAGUUACUAACUUAGUACCAAGUAUGGUGUCCUUGGAAGAGACAAAGUUGUAUACUGGACUUGAAUAUGAUCUGUCUCGAGAGAACCACCGAGAAGUAAUUGCUACAGUUAUAAGGAAACUUCUUAACCACAUACUUGAUAAUUCAGAAGAUGAUACUAAGUCAUUGUUUCUUAUUAUAAAGAUUAUUGGAGACCUUUUACAAUUCCAAGGAUCUCACAAGCAUGAAUUUGACUCCCGAUGGAAAAGCUUCAACUUAGUAAAGAAAUCAAUGGAAAAUCGGCUCCAUGGGAAAAAACAACAUAUCAGAGCACUGUUGAUUGAUAGAGUAAUGUUACAGCAUGAGCUACGGACACUAACUGUUGAGGGUUGUGAAUACAAAAAGAUACAUCAAGAUAUGAUCAGAGAUCUUCUUCGUUUAUCUACAAGUUCAUACAGUCAGGUGAGAAAUAAGGCUCAGCAAACAUUUUUUGCUGCCUUGGGAGCAUAUAACUUCUGUUGCAGAGAUAUCAUUCCCUUGGUUUUGGAGUUCUUAAGGCCUGAUAGACAAGGUGUUACACAGCAACAAUUCAAGGGUGCCUUGUACUGUCUCCUUGGAAAUCACAGUGGUGUGUGCUUGGCAAACCUUCAUGAUUGGGACUGUAUUGUACAGACGUGGCCAGCGAUUGUUUCUUCAGGGCUUAGCCAAGCAAUGUCCCUGGAAAAGCCAUCAAUAGUGAGAUUGUUUGAUGAUCUUGCAGAAAAGAUUCAUAGGCAGUAUGAAACAAUUGGCUUGGACUUCACAAUUCCAAAGUCAUGUGUUGAAAUAGCGGAAUUACUUCAACAGUCAAAAAACCCCUCUAUCAACCAGAUAUUGCUUAGCCCAGAAAAAAUUAAGGAAGGAAUUAAACGCCAACAGGAAAAGAAUGCCGAUGCCCUAAGGAACUAUGAAAAUUUGGUAGACACCUUGCUAGAUGGUGUGGAGCAAAGAAACCUGCCCUGGAAAUUUGAACAUAUAGGCAUUGGGCUUCUGUCUCUACUGCUGAGAGAUGACCGAGUGUUGCCUCUUCGUGCCAUACGGUUUUUUGUUGAGAAUCUCAACCAUGAUGCAAUUGUAGUUCGAAAGAUGGCUAUCUCAGCUGUUGCUGGUAUCCUUAAACAGCUAAAAAGAACCCACAAAAAGCUGACCAUUAACCCCUGUGAAAUCAGUGGAUGCCCUAAACCCACCCAAAUUAUUGCUGGUGAUAGGCCUGAUAAUCAUUGGUUGCAUUAUGACAGCAAAACUAUACCAAGAACUAAAAAAGAAUGGGAGUCAAGUUGCUUUGUGGAAAAAACUCACUGGGGAUACUACACCUGGCCAAAGAAUAUGGUUGUUUAUGCUGGUGUGGAAGAGCAGCCUAAGCUUGGCAGAAGCAGGGAGGAUAUGACAGAGGCAGAACAGAUUAUAUUUGAUCAUUUUUCUGAUCCUAAAUUUGUUGAGCAGUUAAUUACUUUUCUAUCAUUAGAAGACAGAAAAGGAAAAGAUAAGUUUAAUCCACGACGUUUUUGCCUCUUUAAGGGUAUAUUCAGGAAUUUUGAUGAUGCCUUCCUGCCAGUUCUGAAGCCCCAUUUAGAACAUUUGGUUGCAGAUUCACAUGAAAGCACCCAGCGAUGUGUUGCAGAAAUUAUAGCUGGUUUAAUCAGAGGUUCUAAGCACUGGACAUUUGAAAAGGUGGAGAAGCUUUGGGAGCUUCUGUGCCCUCUGCUUAGAACAGCACUGUCCAAUAUUACCGUAGAAACUUAUAAUGACUGGGGAGCUUGUAUAGCAACAUCCUGUGAAAGCAGAGAUCCCCGGAAACUUCACUGGCUUUUUGAACUGCUGUUGGAAUCACCAUUGAGUGGUGAAGGAGGAUCCUUUGUAGAUGCAUGUCGACUUUAUGUACUACAAGGUGGCCUUGCCCAGCAAGAAUGGAGAGUGCCUGAACUAUUGCACAGACUACUGAAGUACUUGGAACCCAAACUCACCCAGGUUUACAAAAAUGUCAGAGAAAGAAUAGGAAGUGUGCUGACCUACAUAUUCAUGAUAGAUGUAUCUUUGCCAAAUACCACACCAACCAUAUCGCCUCAUGUCCCUGAGUUUACUGCUCGAAUUCUGGAGAAAUUGAAACCUCUCAUGGAUGUGGAUGAAGAAAUUCAGAACCAUGUUAUGGAAGAAAAUGGAAUUGGUGAAGAAGAUGAGCGAACUCAGGGCAUUAAACUCUUGAAAACCAUAUUGAAAUGGCUGAUGGCAAGUGCAGGAAGAUCCUUUUCUACAGCAGUUACAGAACAACUUCAGCUUCUACCUUUGUUUUUCAAGAUUGCCCCAGUGGAAAAUGACAAUAGCUACGAUGAACUGAAAAGAGAUGCAAAGUUAUGUUUAUCAUUAAUGUCUCAGGGGUUGCUUUACCCUCAUCAAGUGCCUUUGGUACUUCAGGUGCUAAAACAAACAGCAAGAAGCAGUUCUUGGCAUGCACGAUACACAGUACUGACCUACCUCCAGACCAUGGUAUUUUAUAACCUCUUUAUUUUCCUAAACAAUGAAGAUGCAGUUAAAGAUAUCAGGUGGCUGGUUAUAAGUCUUUUGGAGGACGAACAACUGGAGGUUCGAGAAAUGGCUGCUACUACCUUAAGCGGUCUGCUACAGUGUAACUUUCUUACCAUGGACAGUCCUAUGCAGAUUCAUUUUGAGCAACUUUGCAAAACAAAACUACCUAAGAAAAGAAAGCGAGACCCUGGUUCUGUAGGAGAUACCAUUCCUUCUGCAGAGUUGGUCAAACGCCAUGCUGGGGUGCUAGGACUUGGUGCAUGUGUUCUUUCUAGUCCUUACGAUGUUCCCACCUGGAUGCCCCAGCUCCUCAUGAAUCUCAGUGCACAUCUAAAUGAUCCUCAGCCUAUUGAGAUGACUGUAAAAAAAACCUUAUCCAAUUUCCGAAGGACUCACCAUGACAACUGGCAGGAACAUAAACAGCAAUUCACUGAUGACCAACUGCUUGUUCUCACCGAUCUUCUUGUGUCACCAUGCUAUUAUGCAUAGAAAGAUGACUAGUCCUCACUUCAGGCUCUUUUCAUCAAAAAUUCCACACCCUCAGGUACCAUCUGUGGUGGCUCUCUGCAAGUUUUAAAACUGCCUCUGCUGAGCUCUCAUCAUUUUGGUGGUUUCUGUGUUAGAUCUCGUUAGUCUGCAUUCCACAGCUUCUCAGUUGCCAUUUGAUUUCCCAACUUGUCCGGAAGUGUUUCCAGAAUACUGAUCACUUUUUUUUUUUGAGGCAUCUGACAAAGUCACAAAGUCUCAGACUAGAAAUAAUUACCCAGUAUGAUCAUGGCAUCCAAGACCAGAGUCUCAGAACUCAUUAAGAAACAGUUUACUUGGAAUGGAGAAUACCCAUCUGUAAUACAGGUCCUGUCAUUUCAUUCAUCUCAAAUUAUUUUGAAUUCUUCCCAAAUGGCUGCUGGAUUUAGGUGGUAAUAGGGGCUGUGGGCCAUAAAUCUGAAGCCUUGAGAACCUUGGGUCUGGAGAGCCAUGAAGAGGGAAGGAAAAGAGGGCAAGUCCUGAACCUAACCAAUGACCUGAUGGAUUGCUCGACCAAGACACAGAAGUGAAGUCUGUGUCUGUGCACUUCCCACAGACUGGAGUUUUUGGUGCUGAAUAGAGCCAGUUGCUAAAAAAUUGGGGGUUUGGUGAAGAAAUCUGAUUGUUGUGUGUAUUCAAUGUGUGAUUUUAAAAAUAAACAGCAACAACAAUAAAAACCCUGACUGGCUGUUUUUUCCCUGUAUUCUUUACAACUAUUUUUUGACCCUCUGAAAAUUAUUAUACUUCACCUAAAUGGAAGACUGCUGUGUUUGUGGAAAUUUUGUAAUUUUUUAAUUUAUUUUAUUCUCUCUCCCUUUUUAUUUUGCCUGCAGAAUCGUUGAGAGACUAAUAAGGCUUAAUAUUUAAUUGAUUUGUUUAAUAUGUUAUAUAAAUGUAAAAGAGUGUAUAAACUGUAGAGAUAGCAUUGGCAAGACAUUGUACAGAUGCAACCUUUUACACAACAUCAUUGUGUAAUUUGUAAAGAUUCACGUGUAGUUCUUUAUUAUAGUGAUUUUGGGCUUUGUACCCACUGAAUGCCAUUUUUUGUGUUUUUAAAUUAUUUUCUUUAUCUUGUUACAAAAACUGAGAUGUGGGGUUUUUUUUUUUUCAGUUCACUUAUCAUUAGAAUGUCUGAACUUUUAUGUAACAUUUUUGUGUGCAUCUCUCAAUGCUAACACCACAUGUUUGCCUAUGACAAGUUUAUAGAGUGAAAGGUAUCUUCUGGGUUGAAAUAAUUCACAAAUUGGUGAAUGUCAUCUUGCAACACACCCUGUACAGUCUUCCUUAAAGGAACACUACAGUAUAUUUUUAGUAUCUACAUGCUGAAUGACUGAAUACAGACCUAAGCACAGCAGUGGUCCUGGUACAGUAUUUAAGUGUCGGCAUACACAGGCGUAAUCCCUGUAUAAAGUAGUGCCAAACUGAUUUCAGUUGUGUAACUAGUUUAAAACCCAAUAAAUGGAUUCUUUUUAA